AGAGAGACGCAGCUAGGCCUGCACGGCUGUGGAGAGAUCCUGCCACGGGCCUUGUUCACCAUGUCGGUGCUGGAUGCGCUUUGGGAGGAUCGGGAUGUCCGUUUCGACCUGUCCGCGCAGCAAAUGAAAACAAGACCUGGAGAAGUCCUUAUUGAUUGUUUAGAUUCCAUUGAAGACACCAAAGGAAAUAAUGGAGAUAGAGGUAGACUCUUGGUAACAAAUUUAAGAAUUCUCUGGCACUCUUUGGCAUUAUCAAGAGUCAAUGUUUCUGUCGGUUACAAUUGCAUAUUGAAUAUUACAACAAGGACUGCUAACUCUAAAUUACGAGGCCAAACUGAAGCUCUCUAUAUACUAACAAAAUGUAACAGUACUCGUUUUGAAUUUAUAUUUACAAAUUUGGUUCCUGGAAGCCCUAGACUUUUUACUUCUGUGAUGGCAGUACACAGAGCUUAUGAAACUUCUAAAAUGUAUCGUGAUUUUAAAUUAAGAAGUGCACUAAUUCAGAACAAGCAACUAAGACUGUUGCCACAAGAACAUGUAUAUGAUAAAAUAAAUGGAGUUUGGAAUUUAUCCAGUGAUCAGGGCAAUUUAGGAACCUUUUUUAUUACCAAUGUGAGAAUUGUGUGGCAUGCAAAUAUGAAUGAUAGUUUUAAUGUCAGUAUACCAUAUCUGCAAAUUCGUUCAAUAAAGAUUAGAGAUUCAAAAUUUGGUUUAGCUCUUGUCAUAGAAAGCUCUCAGCAGAGUGGUGGAUAUGUUCUUGGCUUUAAAAUAGAUCCUGUGGAAAAACUACAAGAAUCAGUUAAGGAAAUCAAUUCACUUCACAAAGUCUAUUCUGCCAGUCCCAUAUUUGGAGUUGAUUAUGAGAUGGAAGAAAAGCCCCAGCCGCUCGAAGCUCUGACAGUCGAACAAAUUCAAGAUGAUGUAGAAAUAGACUCUGAUGGUCACACGGAUGCUUUUGUGGCUUAUUUUGCUGAUGGCAAUAAGCAACAAGAUCGUGAACCUGUAUUUUCAGAAGAACUGGGGCUUGCAAUAGAGAAAUUGAAGGAUGGAUUCACCCUACAGGGACUUUGGGAAGUAAUGAGUUGAUUGACCUUGAGUUGAGAUGGAUUUCUAUUAAAGAUAUCUCUAGUUUAAAGAUACUAGUCACCUGCCAUAAGUCAUGGAAUAGUUUUUAUAUUUACAGCUUUUAUAUUUAAAACUUGUAAGAGUUUUUUUAAUGAUUGAGGAAAAAGUCAUUUAGAAAACUUCAGUUUUCGGCCAGCGCGUCGAGGGAGGGGCCAGCGACACAUGGCCUAGUAACCGUCCGGCCGCGGCGCUGGCUUAAGCCAUGGCUGAGGGUAGCUGGAUUCCUCAGGCCCGGGCGCUCCUACAGCAGUGCCUGCACGCCCGGCUGCAAAUUCGCCCAGCCAAUGGGGACGUUGCGGCCCAGUGGGUGGAGGUCCAAAGAGGACUGGUGAUCUACGUGUGCUUUUUCAAGGGAGCUGAUAAAGAACUUCUUCCCAAAAUGGCCGAAGCUGGACUGUACUGCUGCCAUCUCUGGCUCACUGCAACCUCCCUGCCUGAUUCUCCUGCCUCAGCCUGCCGAGUGCCUGCGAUUACAGGCGCGCGCCGCCACACCUGACUGGUUUUCGUAUUUUUUUGGUGGAGACGGGGUUUCGCUGUGUUGGCCGGGCUGGUCUCCAGCUCCUAACCGCGAGUGAUCCGCCAGCCUCGGCCUCCCGAGGUGCCGGGAUUGCAGACGGAGUCUGGUUCACUUAGUGCUCAAUGGUGCCCAGGCUGGAGUGCAGUGGCGUGAUCUCCGCUCGCUACAACCUCCACCUCCCAGCUGCCUGCCUUGGCCUCCCGAAGUGCCAAGAGUGCAGCCUCUGCCCGGCCGCCACCCCGUCUGGGAAGUGAGGAGCGUCUCUGCCUGGCUGCCCAUUGUCUGGGACGUGAGCAGCCCCUCUGCCUGGCUGCCCAGUCUGGAAAGUGAGGAGCGUCUCUGCCCGGCCGCCAUCCCAUCUAGGAAGUGAGGAGCGCCUCUUCCCACCCGCCAUCCCAUCUAGGAAGUGAGGAGCUUCUCUGCCUGGCCGCCCAUCGUCUGAGAUGUGGGGAGCACCUCUGCCCGGCCGCGACCCCAUUUGGGAGGUGAGGAGCAACUCUGCCCAGCCGCCCCGUCUGAGAAGUGAGGAGACCCUCCGCCUGGCAACCGCCCCGUCUGAUAAGUAAGGAGCCCCUCUGCCCAGCAGCCGCCCCGUCUGAGAAGUGAGGAGCCCCUCUGCCCAGCAGCCACCCUGUCUGGGAAGUGAGGAGCGUCUCCGCCCGGCAGCCACCCAGUCCGGGAGGGAGGUGGGGGGGUCAGUCCCCCGUCCGGCCAGCCGCCCCGUCCGGGAGGUGAGGGGCGCCUCUGCCCAGCUGCCCCUACUGGGAAGUGAGGAGCCCCUCUGCCCCGCCAGCCACCCCGUCCGGGAGGGAGGUGGGGGGGUCAGCCCCCCGCCCGGCCAGCCGCCCCGUCCGGGAGGGAGGUGGGGGAUCAGCCCCCCGCCCGGCUAGCCGCCCCGUCCGGGAGGCGAGGGGCGCCUCUGCCCGGCUGCCCCUACUGGGAAGUGAGGAGCCCCUCUGCCCGGCCAGCCGCCCCGUCCAGGAGGGAGGUGGGGGGGUCAGCCCCCCGCCCGGCCAGCCGCCCGGUCCGGGAGGGAGGUGGGGGGGUCAGCCCCCCGCCCGGCCAGCCGCCCCGUCCGGGAGGUUAGGGGCGCCUCUGCCCGGCCGCCCCUACUGGGAAGUGAGGAGCCCCUCUGCCCGGCCACCACCCCGUCUGGGAGGUGUACCCAACAGCUCAUUGAGAGCGGGCGAUGAUGACAGUGGCGGCUUUGUGGAGUGGAGGUGGGGGGAAGGUGGGGAAAAGAUUGAGAAAUCGGAUGGUUGCCGUGUCUGUGUAGAAAGAAGUAGACAUGGGAGACUUUUCAUUUUGUUCUGUACUAAGAAAAAUUCUUACCCUAAAACUUAAAGUAUAAUAAAAAAAAAAAAACUUCAGUUUUCUAAAAAUUAUAUUUAAAAUUGUAAUCAAAAUGUACCUAGUUUAUAAAUGUUUAUUUUGUACUUAAUACCUGUAAAGUCUUAGUUUUCAGACAUUAAGUGACUGUAUCAUGUUCGGUUUAAUAAAGAAUUUAUGCAGCACCA